AUCCCGCGGCUCCUGGAGCCCUGCCGCCCGCCCCCUGCGAACCCAGGCCCCGCCGCCAAUGGCUCGCCCUGCCUCUGCGCCGCUUGGCCCGUCCCCUCUCAAGCAUAUCUCGGAUAACGCCCCUUCCGCACCUUUCACGGGCGGUGGGAGCUGAGGCUCCUGUCGUUAUCUCUGAUCCUUGCACCCUGGCAGGAAGCUGGUAGCUCACACUUUAACGGGAGGCCUUCACAUAUUCCAGAAAAGAAACCACUUUGCAGUGCCAGACUGGAAGAAGUAACGGUCACUCUGAAAACAGGGUGGGAGAGCUGCCUCUCUUUGAACCUCUCCCAGGACCAACUCUAACCCAGGGAGGCAAACUUGGUCGAUGUAAGCGGUGGCUUGGAGACAGAAUCAUCUAAUGGAAAAGAUACACUAGAAGGUGCUGGGGAUACAUCAGAGGUGAUGGAUACUCAGGCGGGCUCCGUGGAUGAAGAGAAUGGCCGACAGUUGGGUGAGGUAGAGCUGCAAUGUGGGAUUUGUACAAAAUGGUUCACGGCUGACACAUUUGGCAUAGAUACCUCAUCCUGUCUACCUUUCAUGACCAACUACAGUUUUCAUUGCAACGUCUGCCAUCACAGUGGGAAUACCUAUUUCCUCCGGAAGCAAGCAAACUUGAAGGAAAUGUGCCUUAGUGCUUUGGCCAACCUGACAUGGCAGUCCCGAACACAGGAUGAACAUCCGAAGACAAUGUUCUCCAAAGAUAAGGAUAUUAUACCAUUUAUUGAUAAAUACUGGGAGUGCAUGACAACCAGACAGAGACCUGGGAAAAUGACUUGGCCAAAUAACAUUGUUAAAACAAUGAGUAAAGAAAGAGAUGUAUUCUUGGUAAAGGAACACCCAGAUCCAGGCAGUAAAGAUCCAGAAGAAGAUUACCCCAAAUUUGGACUUUUGGAUCAGGACCUUAGUAACAUUGGUCCUGCUUAUGACAACCAAAAACAGAGCAGUGCUGUGUCUACUAGUGGGAAUUUAAAUGGUGGAGCCACUUUUGGAGGGGGAAUUGCAGCAGGAAGCAGCGGAAAAGGACGAGGAGCCAAGCGCAAACAGCAGGAUGGAGGGACCACAGGGACCACCAAGAAGGCCCGGAGUGACCCUUUGUUUUCUGCUCAGCGCCUUCCCCCUCAUGGCUACCCAUUGGAACACCCGUUUAACAAAGAUGGCUAUCGGUAUAUUCUAGCUGAGCCUGAUCCGCACGCCCCUGACCCCGAGAAGCUGGAACUUGACUGCUGGGCAGGAAAACCUAUUCCUGGAGACCUCUACAGAGCCUGCUUGUAUGAACGGGUUUUGUUAGCCCUACAUGAUCGAGCUCCCCAGUUAAAGAUCUCAGAUGACCGGCUGACUGUGGUUGGAGAGAAGGGCUACUCUAUGGUGAGGGCCUCUCAUGGAGUACGGAAAGGUGCCUGGUAUUUUGAAAUCACUGUGGAUGAGAUGCCACCAGAUACCGCUGCCAGACUGGGUUGGUCCCAGCCCCUAGGAAACCUUCAAGCUCCUUUAGGUUAUGAUAAAUUUAGCUAUUCUUGGCGGAGCAAAAAGGGAACCAAGUUCCACCAGUCCAUUGGCAAACACUACUCUUCUGGCUAUGGACAGGGAGACGUCCUGGGAUUUUAUAUUAAUCUUCCUGAAGACACAGAGACAGCCAAGUCAUUGCCAGACACAUACAAAGAUAAGGCUUUGAUAAAAUUCAAGAGUUAUUUGUAUUUUGAGGAAAAAGACUUUGUGGAUAAAGCAGAGAAGAGCCUGAAGCAGACUCCCCAUAGUGAGAUAAUAUUUUAUAAAAAUGGUGUCAAUCAAGGUGUGGCUUACAAAGAUAUUUUUGAGGGGGUUUACUUCCCAGCCAUCUCACUGUACAAGAGCUGCACGGUUUCCAUUAACUUUGGACCAUGCUUCAAGUAUCCUCCGAAGGAUCUCACUUACCGCCCUAUGAGUGACAUGGGCUGGGGCGCCGUGGUAGAGCACACCCUGGCUGACGUCUUGUAUCACGUGGAGACAGAAGUGGAUGGGAGGCGCAGUCCCCCAUGGGAACCCUGACCAGGUCCCUCUUUUCUGUCAAGGACUUUCUGGGAAUAAUACUGGGGGUUUUGUUUUUGUUUUUGAACUGUCUCAAAUGUUCUCCCAAAGAUGCUAAAAACACAGCCUCUCCUUUUAGCAAGUUAAAAGGCUGGGUAGGACUGCGGGAGACUGCCUGCCUUUCACCAUUUUCUCCCCACUUCCAGUGACUGCUCUUAUUUUGUGUACCAUAAGCCAACAACCGCUGACUCCAGGAUUGCAUAAGCCCCCUGUGAAAUCGGUGCUGUACUGCAUACCCUGCCAGCUGUGACUUGUUAUCCUACUAUAUUUUCUAAGGAGUGAAUAAUAUUGUCCGAGUAACUAACUUAUUUAAAAGACAUUUCCUUCUGUGGGCAUUGACUGUAUCCCACCUGUUUUCCAAGGAAAUGGUAACCUGUUUCUGAGAACACCUGAAAUCAAUGGCUAUACAUUCCAAACCAAUCUAAACGCUAUUUCCUUUUGGUGUGGGUUUGGUUUUGUUCAUUUUGAAAUACACUUUUGAACACUGAGAUCCGUAAAACUACUAGAUCUCUGGAAGUGUAAUUGUGAAAGAAACUUGCUUGCAGCUUUAACAAAAUGAGAAACUUCCCAAAUAAAACUUGUUUUGAAGUUUAUGUGACACUUUGCUUCCCUUCAGAUUGGGUGCCUCUUGGUGACAGUGUUCAGAAAUGUAAGCAGCACGAGGAAGGGAGCUGGCACUGGGAGGAAGAGCCGGGUUUCUGAGUUGUGUUUUGGCUGCUUUCCUAUUGCUCCCAUUCUUGCCAAUCAGCCACCCCCUUUCCUGUGAAAAUCUGCCACCUUGAGGAGAGGAACAAGAGUUUAAAAGGGCUAAUGAUCUCCCUCCCGGUCUUCCCUUGGAACAUGGAUGUUGAUAUAUGUGCGGGUGGUUUCCUGUCUUGCUUAUCUUCCUUUGCCCUGAGCUGAUGGCUAAAGGGCAGUUUUCGGACUAUUAAAGACUGAAAUGUAAGAAUGAGCCUUCUAGGCUGGGCGC